GCUUCUGCUCUGGGCACGCAUGGCGCCCGCACACGGAGUCUGACCUGAUGCAGACGCAAGGGGGUUAAUAUGAACGCCCCUCUCGGUGGAAUCUGGCUCUGGCUCCCUCUGCUCUUGACCUGGCUCACCCCCGAGGUCAACUCUUCAUGGUGGUACAUGAGAGCUACAGGUGGCUCCUCCAGGGUGAUGUGCGAUAAUGUGCCAGGCCUGGUGAGCAGCCAGCGGCAGCUGUGUCACCGACAUCCAGAUGUGAUGCGUGCCAUUAGCCAGGGCGUGGCCGAGUGGACAGCAGAAUGCCAGCACCAGUUCCGCCAGCACCGCUGGAAUUGCAACACCCUGGACAGGGAUCACAGCCUUUUUGGCAGGGUCCUACUCCGAAGUAGUCGGGAAUCUGCCUUUGUUUAUGCCAUCUCCUCAGCUGGAGUUGUAUUUGCCAUCACCAGGGCCUGUAGCCAAGGAGAAGUAAAAUCCUGUUCCUGUGAUCCAAAGAAGAUGGGAAGCGCCAAGGACAGCAAAGGCAUUUUUGAUUGGGGUGGCUGCAGUGAUAACAUUGACUAUGGGAUCAAAUUUGCCCGCGCAUUUGUGGAUGCAAAGGAAAGGAAAGGAAAGGAUGCCAGAGCCCUGAUGAAUCUUCACAACAACAGAGCUGGCAGGAAGGCUGUAAAGCGGUUCUUGAAACAAGAGUGCAAGUGCCACGGGGUGAGCGGCUCAUGUACUCUCAGGACAUGCUGGCUGGCCAUGGCCGACUUCAGGAAAACGGGCGAUUAUCUCUGGAGGAAGUACAAUGGGGCCAUCCAGGUGGUCAUGAACCAGGAUGGCACAGGUUUCACUGUGGCUAACGAGAGGUUUAAGAAGCCAACGAAAAAUGACCUCGUGUAUUUUGAGAAUUCUCCAGACUACUGUAUCAGGGACCGAGAGGCAGGCUCCCUGGGUACAGCAGGCCGUGUGUGCAACCUGACUUCCCGGGGCAUGGACAGCUGUGAAGUCAUGUGCUGUGGGAGAGGCUACGACACCUCCCAUGUCACCCGGAUGACCAAGUGUGGGUGUAAGUUCCACUGGUGCUGCGCCGUGCGCUGUCAGGACUGCCUGGAAGCUCUGGAUGUGCACACAUGCAAGGCCCCCAAGAACGCUGACUGGACAACCGCUACAUGACCCCAGCAGGCGUCACCAUCCACCUUCCCUUCUACAAGGACUCCAUUGGAUCUGCAAGAACACUGGACCUUUGGGUUCUUUCUGGGGGGAUAUUUCCUAAGGCAUGUGGCCUUUAUCUCAACGGAAGCCCCCUCUUCCUCCCUGGGGGCCCCAGGAUGGGGGGGCCACACGCUGCACCUAAAGCCUACCCUAUUCUAUCCAUCUCCUGGUGUUCUGCAGUCAUCUCCCCUCCUGGCGAGUUCUCUUUGGAAAUAGCAUGACAGGCUGUUCAGCCGGGAGGGUGGUGGGCCCAGACCACUGUCUCCACCCACCUUGACGUUUCUUCUUUCUAGAGCAGUUGGCCAAGCAGAAAAAAAAGUGUCUCAAAGGAGCUUUCUCAAUGUCUUCCCACAAAUGGUCCCAAUUAAGAAAUUCCAUACUUCUCUCAGAUGGGAACAGUAAAGAAAGCAGAAUCAACUGCCCCUGACUUAACUUUAACUUUUGAAAAGACCAAGACUUUUGUCUGAUCAAGUGGUUUUACAGCUACCACCCUUAGGGGUAAUUGGUAAUUACCUGGAGAAGAAUGGCUUUCAAUACCCUUUUAAGUUUAAAAUGUGUAUUUUUCAAGGCAUUUAUUGCCAUAUUAAAAUCUGAUGUAACAAGGUGGGGACGUGUGUCCUUUGGUACUAUGGUGUGUUGUAUCUUUGUAAGAGCAAAAGCCUCAGAAAGGGAUUGCUUUGCAUUACUGUCCCCUUGAUAUAAAAAAUCUUUAGGGAAUGAGAGUUCCUUCUCACUUAGAAUCCGAAGGGAAUUAAAAAGAAGAUGAAUGGUCUGGCAAUAUUCUGUAACUAUUGGGUGAAUAUGGUGGAAAAUAAUUUAGUGGAUGGAAUAUCAGAAGUAUAUCUGUACAGAUCAAGAAAAAAAGGGAGAAUAAAAUUCCUAUCUCAUAUUAUGCAUGUGACCCAUGGAAUCUCAUAACUGAAAGACUUGAAGGAUGAAAAUUUUGGGGAUACAAGAUUGGUGAACUAAAAUGCUGACAGAGAGGUUUCCAGAGCUAACUCGUGCCUGGGGCGGCCUUACAAUAAGCAGAUGCCUGAAAGAAGUCGGCCACGUCCGCCGUCUGCUAAUGCCCAUCACCCUUCAAGCCCAGUUUAAAGACCUGUCAUAUUUAAUUGUAUUUAUUUGAUGCUUACAAGAUGAUGUGAUACUGUAGCCUAAAGCAAAUGACACAUAGCAUUGCUUAUAAAGUUGGUAACCCUGCUAUAUUAUAUUGCAAACAAAUCGUAACUUGGAGACUAUGUUUAAGGGACUCAACUGUAAUUAUGGGAGCAUCAGUAUGCAAAUAGUGGUUGGCUUCUGCCAUCAGCCAAAAGAUGACAUUCAGGGAAAAUGGAGAGGCUGCCUGCACCGUUUUUUUAUGUUAAAUGAAAGAAAGGUGAAAUAGCUACUUCUCGUCUUCUUGAAAAAUUUGGUUCUUAUUCUGUAUAUGACUUCCUUACAGUGCUACAUUAACAGGAUAUUUCAUUACAUGCAUCUGGUAUCAAAUUAUUGGUUCUUCCUCAUUCUUUAAUACCAUACAGUAAGGUCAUUUAGACUGAGACUCGUACAAAACAACCUACUGGAGUACUUUGCCAUAGUUAACAUUUGCCUCCAGCCCUCUUAAAAAUGUCAGAAUUCAUCCCCUUUCCCUCAUUCCCAAAUUGUUGUCUAACUUUUCCAAAGUGACUCUUUCCUCCUUUUAUUCUAUGGAUUCGGAUGGUGGGAACAGUGGAAUGACAGUAGCUGCUCUGAGCUUGGUGUGAAGAAGGCCAGGCACAUGGGCAGCUGCUCAGUCUUCAGUUACCCUGAAGGUUGGUGUGAAUUCCUUCAUGAGAGUGCGAAGGCACUUUCAUGGGGGUCCCACAGCCAUCAGCCCUUCCUCCUGCUGGAUGAACUGUGAAAUCAUCAAUCCAGGCUGUGUUUCAAAUUGGAAAGGAUCUUAGGAGACAUCUCAGCUUCCUUUAGUUUGGGGAAAUUGAGACCAAGAGAGGCGAAGGGAUUGGUGCACAUAUCAGGCAUUGCCCAAUGCUCCAUCACAAAUAGGACCACACUCUUGAGUGUUUGAGAUAGUGUAGGACUUUAUCCAUUAAAUGAAACUAGCUUCUCCCAGAAUUAACUCAGUGGAUUUUAAAUAAUUUUAGCUUCCAAUGGUGUGUUUGCUACUUUUUUUAUGCCUGGUAUGUUUAGAUCUGACAUUCUUUUUAUGCUGAGAUAUAUCCCUCCUGGUAAGUAGCAAGGGGACAAGGAUAUCCACGUAGGAACCUACAUAAAUUGUCCUAAUCCAUAAGGGAGAUUAUGGCAACCAUCGCAAGUGGCAGUGGGUCCUGCCACUGAGGUGGGAAAAAUAAGAGAAUGAAAUAUUGCUAUCGGCUUUUACUUCUGAAAGAGGAAAUGUCUAUUGUUCGGGAAAAAAAUUACACAACAAAUGAAGGUAAUUUUAAACUCCUUUGCCUUAGAGCUUGGUAGAGGAUCAGUAUUCCAGGAACCUGAAAUACACUGAAACUCUCAAUUAUCUGAGGCUUUUAAGGGGAAUAUAUGGCACAAAUUAGCCAAAACAAAAUAAUUGGGAAAUCCCCUUAUAAAUUCCCUCUUUAUUAAAAUCUUACUAUAAAUUGAAGUUUUCUAGGUCCAAGAUAAUGUCCAUUAAUUUUCUACAAUAUCUGAAAAAGUUUCCACAAUAGGACAU